GCCAUGCAGAAAAGGUGAGGGUUUGCAAAGGGUGUAGCCUCUGGUCCUUUUGUUACUUGGGUGGGGAAAAUUAGCGUUUUCCUUUCAGUUUAGUUCUAGGAAGUCAGGGUGAAUUGGCCUUAGGCCCUGCCUCCAGACCCUGUUCUCCUGCCUCACCACCUCUCUGAUUCUCUUUUCUGUGGUCACAUUUCUCUGGGGCUACAGCCAGGGAAGGUUUUCUGAUUUCAGUGACCCAUGCGAUUAAAUAAUCCAGGAGAGCCUCCUCAUCUCAAGGUCCUUAAUCUAAGCACAUCAGCAGAGUCCCUUUACCGCGCACGUGCCUUAACACCUCAAACUGCAGAAACAGAUGCCAUUCGGUUUUUGGUUGGGACGCAGUCUCUUAAAUAUGAUAAUCAGAUCCAUAUCAUAGAUUUUGACGAUGAAAACAACAUUAUAAAUAAAAAUGUCCUCCUCCAUCAAGCGGGUGAAAUCUGGCAUAUUAGCGCUAGCCCUGCAGACAGAGGUGUGCUGACGACCUGCUACAACAGAACAUUUUGUUGUGUGCUGUCUCUGGAUUCCUUUGGUGCUCUUGGGAAGUCAGCUGCCCAACUGUUCAUAGCACUGGCAACCUCUUCAGACAGCAAAGUCCUGACAUGUGCAGCCGUGUGGAGGAUGCCGAAGGAAUUGGAAUCAGGCAGCCACGAGUCCCCUGAUGAUUCAUCCAGCACUGCACAGACCCUGGAGCUGCUCUGUCACCUUGACAACACAGCCCAUGGCAACAUGGCCUGUGUCGUGUGGGAGCCAAUGGGAGAUGGGAAGAAAAUCAUUUCCUUGGCUGAUAACCAUAUCCUGCUGUGGGAUUUACAGGAAAGCUCGAGCCAGGCUGUGCUGGCCAGCUCAGCGUCCCUGGAAGGGAAGGGACAACUGAAGUUCACCUCAGGACGGUGGAGCCCACAUCAUAACUGCACCCAGGUGGCCACAGCGAACGACACCACCCUCCGUGGCUGGGACACCCGGAGCAUGAGCCAGAUCUACUGCAUAGAGAAUGCCCACGGACAGCUGGUGCGGGACCUUGACUUUAAUCCCAAUAAGCAGUACUACUUGGCCAGCUGCGGAGACGACUGUAAGGUGAAGUUCUGGGACACCCGAAAUGUCACCGAACCCGUGAAGACCCUGGAGGAGCACUCCCACUGGGUGUGGAACGUCCGCUACAACCACUCUCAUGACCAGCUGGUCCUCACGGGCAGCAGUGACAGCAGAGUCAUCCUUUCCAACAUGGUGUCCAUCUCGUCGGAGCCCUUCGGCCACUUGGUAGACGACGAUGACAUCAGUGACCAGGAGGACCACCGUUCUGAAGAGAAGAGCAAGGAGCCCCUGCAGGACAACGUGAUCGCCACCUACGAGGAGCACGAGGACAGCGUCUAUGCCGUGGACUGGUCCUCGGCUGACCCGUGGCUGUUUGCCUCCCUGAGCUAUGACGGGAGGCUCGUGAUCAACAGGGUGCCCAGGGCCCUGAAGUACCACAUCCUGCUAUGACUCCCGGGCCUGGGUUAUCCAGGUCCCAUUGAGUGGUUUUCCUCUUGGCAGAUUCUCAAACAGUCGCAGCUCUUUGGAGGUGACUCGUGUUCCAGGUGGAUCCCUCUCUGGGAGAGCCGCUGUUCCCUUCCUGUAGCAGCAGCAUUUAUGAAUGGGGUGAAUGGGGCUAUUGUCGACGGCACAGCUAAUGCCCGAACCCAGCCCCUGUCGGCAGAGACAGAGCCCCACAUUAUUAUGUGAAUAACAAUGUUUUCUGUUUUAAGGGUGUCAGGAGUUUCGCUUUUUAAAAAAAUGUCUGUUCCUGCAAUAGUAACUCUUCUUUCUCUUGAGAGUAAAAAAUGAAAUAAAAUAAAUCCACGCUGCA